AUGCUGACUCAUGUGCCCGCAGCUAGCAGGAGCUGGCAGCAUGGGCUCCCCAGGGGCUACGACAGGCUGGGGGCUUCUGGAUUAUAAGACGGAGAAGUAUGUGAUGACCAGGAACUGGCGGGUGGGCGCCCUGCAGAGGCUGCUGCAGUUUGGGAUCGUGGUCUAUGUGGUAGGGUAAGAGAGAAGAGCUUUUGGCCAGGCUGGAGGGGCAAGGGAAGAGGUGGGGGGUGGGGCUUGGUCCUGCUGGGUUGAAGUUGAGGGUUGGGCUGUUUAGGGGCUGGAGUGGAAGGGGGCAGAUUGGGACGGGGUUGGGGAGAGCUAGGCGAUACAAGACAGGAGAGCAAGAACAAGCUGUGUGUUUGUCCUGUGUGUCCACUUGCCUCCUUCCCAGGCCCCCACCCAGGCCCCACCCAGGGGGCACAUGACAUAGUCCUUAACAUCUGUGAGAGCUGGAGCACUAGGCCCCCAGAGAGACCACCAGCUGUAUCUCGGGUGGGCUCUCCUCGCCAAAAAAGGCUACCAGGAGCGGGACCUGGAACCCCAGUUUUCCAUCAUCACCAAACUCAAAGGGGUUUCCGUCACUCAGAUCAAGGAGCUUGGAAACCGGCUGUGGGAUGUGGCCGACUUCGUGAAGCCACCUCAGGGAGAGAACGUGUUCUUCUUGGUGACCAACUUCCUUGUGACGCCAGCCCAAGUUCAGGGCAGAUGCCCAGAGGUGUAAAAACAGGCCAGUGUGUGGUGUUCAAUGGGACCCACAGGACCUGUGAGAUCUGGAGUUGGUGCCCCGUGGAGAGUGGCGUUGUGCCCUCGAGGCCCCUGCUGGCCCAGGCCCAGAACUUCACACUGUUCAUCAAAAACACAGUCACCUUCAGCAAGUUCAACUUCUCUAAGUCCAAUGCCUUGGAGACCUGGGACCCCACCUAUUUUAAGCACUGCCGCUAUGAACCACAAUUCAGCCCCUACUGUCCCGUGUUCCGCAUUGGGGACCUCGUGGCCAAGGCUGGAGGGACCUUCGAGGACCUGGCGUUGCUGGGUGGCUCUGUAGGCAUCAGAGUUCACUGGGAUUGUGACCUGGACACCGGGGACUCUGGCUGCUGGCCUCACUACUCCUUCCAGCUGCAGGAGAAGAGCUACAACUUCAGGACAGCCACUCACUGGUGGGAGCAACCGGGUGUGGAGGCCCGCACCCUGCUCAAGCUCUAUGGAAUCCGCUUCGACAUCCUCGUCACCGGGCAGGCAGGGAAGUUCGGGCUCAUCCCCACGGCCGUCACACUGGGCACCGGGGCAGCUUGGCUGGGCGUGGUCACCUUUUUCUGUGACCUGCUACUGCUGUAUGUGGAUAGAGAAGCCCAUUUCUACUGGAGGACAAAGUAUGAGGAGGCCAAGGCCCCGAAAGCAACCGCCAACUCUGUGUGGAGGGAGCUGGCCCUUGCAUCCCAAGCCCGACUGGCCGAGUGCCUCAGACGGAGCUCAGCACCUGCACCCACGGCCACUGCUGCUGGGAGUCAGACACAGACACCAGGAUGGCCCUGUCCAAGUUCUGACACCCACUUGCCAACCCAUUCCGGGAGCCUGUAGCCGUUCCCUGCUGGUUGAGAGUUGGGGGCUGGGAAGGGCGGGGCCCUGCCUGGGGAUCUCAAGGAUGAGGCCCCAGCAUGGAGGAUUGGGGGUAGAAUUCCACCCUUGAACCCCAGCAGACAGUCCCUCCCCUGACUCCCACCUUGGUAGGGUGCUGCCUCAGGGAGCCAUAGAAGUCGGCUGUGUUUUGAGACGGCGACAGAACCUGACCCGUGGAGACUGGGAGAGCCCAGCAGGCACCUGUAUUGCAGGGCUCCGACUGCAUGUGGCAGGGGCUCCUGCUGCGUCUGGGCCUGGAGGUCUCUCUCCCAGUGCUCUGUCCCCAGUGUUCCUAGCAGAGGUAUGCUUACCAGCUGUCAGCACAGACCCUCCUGCUGCCUGGGUCCUGGCCCUCCUCCCCCAUCUGCACCCCCAUCAUAGGUAGAGACCCCACCCUCCCAUCGGUCCUACAUGGGGCUGUGCAGCUGGAGCCAAAAAGGCAAGGUAGAAAGAGGAGUGAUGGGGGAGGGGGAUUGUUUCAGCUUCUCUGGUGCUGUGAUGCCCCAGGAGAGUCCUAAUCUAGGGAAUGGGGUGGAGUAGGCAGAUAAUCCACCUCCCUAUCCCCCAGGCAAGGGCGGAGCAUGUGUCUUGGGCCCACACCUGCUUAGUUUAUGAGGACCGGCUGCUUUCCAGUGGUAGCCCUUUUGCCAUGGAGGUCUGGGAGAGAGAGCAGAGGGCGGCAGGGCUAAGUUGGUGAUCAUUGGGUUCUUCAGGACCUUCUAUAUCCCUCCUCGGUAACCCCCCAGCCCAACCCCUUGGAAUCUUUCCUCCAGGCUUCCUGAGAGCCCUGGGGGUGGGAGGCUGUGGGAGGCUGUACAUCUGAAAUUCACUUCAGUCCAAGUCAUACCUAGGAAGCUGUCUGGGCAGCUGCUCGAGGGAGGCCCUGGCUCUGAUCCCAGGCUGGAUGGAGUGGCUGGAAGGAAUGGUUCCAAACAACACCACCGAGAUCUCCCUCAGGCUGGCCAGGUUUUGCAGCUGGAAUUCUCCUCUUGGUCCCAGGGCGGGGCAGGGAAUUCUAAGUGUCCACCCCAGGGAGGCAAGGGGCUGCUUUCCACUGUGGGUACCUGGUGAUCAGGGCAAGCUGUGGAGGGCCAGGGGUGGGGCUGAGACUGGGCUGACAUCUAGAAUCACCUGCCACCUGGAGCCUCAGUAAAAUGCCUGGGGUCCCUGCUGCCUCUCAAUCUCCAGAGCCAUGUCCAUGGGGAGGUGGGCUCUGAAGGGCGAAGGUGGGAGAGCAGGGCCCCUGAGGCCUGGGUAUCCAAGGAGGGGCACGUGCACCUGAUUCUCCUUGGGGCCCAGAGGAAGCUGAUGUCAUGGCUGGACAAAGUCACGGAGUAAAGCCAGCAAAGCCA